AGCCGGGGGAAGGGGUCCAUGAGGCCGGGCGAGAUCCGGUUCGUUUCCGGAGGGUCGGUGGGCACGGGGCGGCCCGAGUCUGGUUCCUGGACGCGUAUGCCCGCGGAACUGCUGCACUCGGCCUGAGGGGGCGGCGGCCGUCACAGUUCCUGGCCCGCGGGAAGGCCCCGUUCUUGGAGGAAGUUGGCCCCUCUUCGUGUCCGGGGAGGUGGGCGAGCCUUUGCCCUCGCUUCUGUUACCCAGGAAUCUAAACCUCAAGUUACAAUCUCGACAAUACUGACUCCUGCAAUUCACUCUACUGAUCUGUCACCGCCACAAGGAUAGACGGUCGCGGGCCCCUCCCUACCCAAAUGGUUUCAGAGGCUGUGGUGAAUCACCAGGAUUUUCAACUGAGAAAUUUAAGAAUAAUUGAACCUAACGAGGUGACACACUCAGGAGACACAGGUGUGGAAACAGACGGCAGAAUGCCUCCAAAGGUGACUUCAGAGCUGCUUCGGCAGCUGAGACAAGCCAUGAGGAACUCUGAGUAUGUGACCGAACCGAUCCAGGCCUACAUCAUCCCAUCGGGAGAUGCUCAUCAGAGUGAGUAUAUUGCUCCAUGUGACUGUCGGCGGGCUUUUGUCUCUGGAUUCGAUGGCUCUGCGGGCACAGCCAUCAUCACAGAAGAGCAUGCAGCCAUGUGGACUGACGGGCGCUACUUUCUCCAGGCUGCCAAGCAAAUGGACAGCAACUGGACACUUAUGAAGAUGGGUCUGAAGGACACACCAACUCAGGAAGACUGGCUGGUGAGUGUGCUUCCUGAAGGAUCCAGGGUUGGUGUGGACCCCUUGAUCAUUCCUACAGAUUAUUGGAAGAAAAUGGCCAAAGUUCUGAGAAGUGCCGGCCAUCACCUCAUUCCUGUCAAGGAGAACCUCGUUGACAAAAUCUGGACAGACCGUCCUGAGCGCCCUUGCAAGCCUCUCCUCACACUGGGCCUGGAUUACACAGGCAUCUCCUGGAAGGACAAGGUUGCAGACCUUCGGUUGAAAAUGGCUGAGAGGAACGUCAUGUGGUUUGUGGUCACUGCCUUGGAUGAGAUUGCGUGGCUAUUUAAUCUCCGAGGAUCAGAUGUGGAGCACAAUCCAGUAUUUUUCUCCUACGCAAUCAUAGGACUAGAGACGAUCAUGCUCUUCAUUGAUGGUGACCGCAUAGACGCCCCCAGUGUGAAGGAGCACCUGCUUCUUGACUUGGGUCUGGAAGCCGAAUACAGGAUCCAGGUGCAUCCCUACAAGUCCAUCCUGAGCGAGCUCAAGGCCCUGUGUGCUGACCUCUCCCCAAGGGAGAAGGUGUGGGUCAGUGACAAGGCCAGCUAUGCUGUGAGCGAGACCAUCCCCAAGGACCACCGCUGCUGUAUGCCUUACACCCCCAUCUGCAUCGCCAAAGCUGUGAAGAAUUCAGCUGAGUCAGAAGGCAUGAGGCGGGCUCACAUUAAAGAUGCUGUUGCUCUCUGUGAACUCUUUAACUGGCUGGAGAAAGAGGUUCCCAAAGGUGGUGUGACAGAGAUCUCAGCUGCUGACAAAGCUGAGGAGUUUCGCAGGCAACAGGCAGACUUUGUGGACCUGAGCUUCCCAACAAUUUCCAGUACGGGACCCAACGGCGCCAUCAUUCACUACGCGCCAGUCCCUGAGACGAAUAGGACCUUGUCCCUGGAUGAGGUGUACCUUAUUGACUCGGGUGCUCAAUACAAGGAUGGCACCACAGAUGUGACGCGGACAAUGCAUUUUGGGACCCCUACAGCCUACGAGAAGGAAUGCUUCACAUAUGUCCUCAAGGGCCACAUAGCUGUGAGUGCAGCCGUUUUCCCGACUGGAACCAAAGGUCACCUUCUUGACUCCUUUGCCCGUUCAGCUUUAUGGGAUUCAGGCCUAGAUUACUUGCACGGGACUGGACAUGGUGUUGGGUCUUUUUUGAAUGUCCAUGAGGGUCCUUGCGGCAUCAGUUACAAAACAUUCUCUGAUGAGCCCUUGGAGGCAGGCAUGAUUGUCACUGAUGAGCCCGGGUACUAUGAAGAUGGGGCUUUUGGAAUUCGCAUUGAGAAUGUUGUCCUUGUGGUUCCUGUGAAGACCAAGUAUAAUUUUAAUAACCGGGGAAGCCUGACCUUUGAACCUCUAACAUUGGUUCCAAUUCAGACCAAAAUGAUAGAUGUGGAUUCUCUUACAGACAAAGAGUGCGACUGGCUCAACAAUUACCACCUGACCUGCAGGGAUGUGAUUGGGAAGGAAUUGCAGAAACAGGGCCGCCAGGAAGCUCUCGAGUGGCUCAUCAGAGAGACGCAACCCAUCUCCAAACAGCAUUAAUAAAUACCUCCCCGGUUUUGUUUUUGUAAAAUGCUCUGGAGGAAGGAAGAAACGUGGCAGAUCCCUGACAUCUUUCCCCUUUCCUUUCCUUCUUCCCUACCUCCCCUUUUUACUUUAGACUUUAAGAAGAACAGAAAAUCUUCUUAUCCUCUUUGAUAUUUUAUUGCAAACACUCAGUCUUUUAUGAUUUUUUAAUUGUUGAGAACAAGCCAAGAAUAAAAUUGCUGCACCAGAAGGAGGGUCCCUCCAAAGUUGAACACUUGGUGAAAGGAAGAUGCCCCGACUUCUUUGGCCAGUGAUGGGGAAUCAGUGAGUGCUCCAUGAUGGUCAUGUUCCAGGUGCUAGUACAUCAUUCAUGAUCACCUUAAUGCUCAUGAGACUAUAUUUAUGAUCAGUGAAUAAAAAUGUCAGAACUGUG